ACACCCAGCUGCCUGAGACCCUCCUUCAACCUCCCUAGAGGACAGCCCCACUCUGCCUCCUGCUCCCCCAGGGCAGCACCAUGUGGCCCCUGUGGCUCUGCUGGGCACUCUGGGUGCUGCCCCUGGCUGGCCCCGGGGCGGCCCUGACCGAGGAGCAGCUCCUGGGCAGCCUGCUGCGGCAGCUGCAGCUCAGCGAGGUGCCCGUACUGGACAGGGCCGACAUGGAGAAGCUGGUCAUCCCCGCCCACGUGAGGGCCCAGUAUGUAGUCCUGCUGCGGCGCAGCCACGGGGACCGCUCCCGCGGAAAGAGGUUCAGCCAGAGCUUCCGAGAGGUGGCCGGCAGGUUCCUGGCGUCGGAGGCCAGCACACACCUGCUGGUGUUCGGCAUGGAGCAGCGGCUGCCGCCCAACAGCGAGCUGGUGCAGGCCGUGCUGCGGCUCUUCCAGGAGCCGGUCCCCAAGGCCGCGCUGCACAGGCACGGGCGGCUGUCCCCGCGCAGCGCCCAGGCCCGGGUGACCGUCGAGUGGCUGCGCGUCCGCGACGACGGCUCCAACCGCACCUCCCUCAUCGACUCCAGGCUGGUGUCCGUCCACGAGAGCGGCUGGAAGGCCUUCGACGUGACCGAGGCCGUGAACUUCUGGCAGCAGCUGAGCCGGCCCCGGCAGCCGCUGCUGCUACAGGUGUCGGUGCAGAGGGAGCAUCUGGGCCCGCUGGCGUCCGGCGCCCACAAGCUGGUCCGCUUUGCCUCGCAGGGGGCGCCAGCCGGGCUUGGGGAGCCCCAGCUGGAGCUGCACACCCUGGACCUCAGGGACUAUGGAUAUGUUUAUUCAUCUUCUCACAAAUAUCCAGCUUUUAGAACAUAGUGAGAGCUGGAUCAUAAACCUCCCUCCCAGGUGCCCACUAAGCUGUGCCCCAGGCCUUCUGACUUCAGCCUCCCAGAUGACCUCUGACCCUGCUCUCCUUGCCCACACAGAGCUCAGGGCGACUGUGACCCUGAAGCACCAAUGACCGAGGGCACCCGCUGCUGCCGCCAGGAGAUGUACAUUGACCUGCAGGGGAUGAAGUGGGCCAAGAACUGGGUGCUGGAGCCCCCGGGCUUCCUGGCUUACGAGUGUGUGGGCACCUGCCAGCAGCCCCCGGAGGCCCUGGCCUUCAAUUGGCCAUUUCUGGGGCCGCGACAGUGUAUCGCCUCGGAGACUGCCUCGCUGCCCAUGAUCGUCAGCAUCAAGGAGGGAGGCAGGACCAGGCCCCAGGUGGUCAGCCUGCCCAACAUGAGGGUGCAGAAGUGCAGCUGUGCCUCGGAUGGGGCGCUCGUGCCAAGGAGGCUCCAGCCAUAGGCGCCUGGUGUAUCCAUUGAGCCCUCUAACUGAACGUGUGCAUAGAGGUGGUCUUAAUGUAGGUCUUAACUUUAUACUUAGCAAGUUACUCCAUCCCAAUUUAGUGCUCCUGUGUGACCUUCGCCCUGUGUCCUUCCAUUUCCUGUCUUUCCCGUCCAUCACCCAUCCUAAGCACUUACGUGAGUAAAUAAUGCAGCUCAGAUGCUGAGCUCUAGUAGGAAAUGCUGGCAUGCUGAUUACAAGAUACAGCUGAGCAAUGCACACAUUUUCAGCUGGGAGUUUCUGUUCUCUGGCAAAUUCUUCACUGAGUCUGGAACAAUAAUACCCUAUGAUUAGAACUGGGGAAACAGAACUGAAUUGCUGUGUUAUAUGAGGAAUUAAAACCUUCAAAUCUCUAUUUCCCCCAAAUACUGACCCAUUCUGGACUUUUGUAAACAUACCUAGGCCCCUGUUCCCCUGAGAGGGUGCUAAGAGGAAGGAUGAAGGGCUUCAGGCUGGGGGCAGUGGACAGGGAAUUGGGAUACCUGGAUUCUGGUUCUGACAGGGCCACAAGCUAGGAUCUCUAACAAACGCAGAAGGCUUUGGCUCGUCAUUUCCUCUUAAAAAGGAGGAGCUGGGCUUCAGCUCUAAGAACUUCAUUGCCCUGGGGAUCAGACAGCCCCUACCUACCCCUGCCCACUCCUCUGGAGACUGAGCCUUGCCCGUGCAUAUUUAGGUCAUUUCCCACACUGUCUUAGAGAACUUGUCACCAGAAACCACAUGUAUUUGCAUGUUUUUUGUUAAUUUAGCUAAAGCAAUUGAAUGUAGAUACUCAGAAGAAAUAAAAAAUGAUGUUUCA